GCUCCUCCUUCGCGGCGGUACCGCCUCUGUUUCUGCGGCGAUUGAACAGCCGAGCUUUGCGGCCGGGAUCGCGGAAAGUGAUGGCUGUCGUCCCGGCGUCUCUCUCAGGACAGGACGUGGGAUCAUUUGCAUAUCUUACAAUUAAAGACAGAAUACCACAGAUCUUAACUAAGGUUAUUGAUACAUUGCAUCGACAUAAAAGUGAAUUUUUUGAGAAACACGGAGAGGAAGGCGUGGAAGCUGAAAAGAAAGCUAUCUCUCUCCUUUCUAAAUUACGGAAUGAAUUGCAAACAGAUAAACCAUUUAUCCCCUUGGUUGAGAAAUUUGUUGAUACUGAUAUAUGGAAUCAGUACCUAGAAUAUCAACAGAGUCUUUUAAAUGAAAGUGAUGGAAAAUCAAGAUGGUUCUACUCACCGUGGUUGUUGGUAGAAUGUUACAUGUAUCGAAGAAUUCAUGAAGCAAUUAUCCAGAGUCCACCAAUCGAUUACUUUGAUGUAUUUAAAGAAUCAAAAGAGCAAAAUUUCUAUGGGUCACAGGAAUCCAUCAUUGCUUUAUGUACUCACCUGCAACAAUUGAUAAGAACUAUUGAAGACCUAGAUGAAAAUCAGCUGAAAGAUGAGUUUUUUAAACUUCUGCAGAUUUCACUGUGGGGAAAUAAGUGUGAUCUGUCUCUCUCAGGUGGAGAAAGUAGUUCUCAGAAUACCAAUGUACUAAAUUCAUUGGAAGACCUAAAACCUUUCAUUUUAUUGAAUGAUAUGGAACAUCUUUGGUCAUUGCUUAGCAAUUGCAAGAAAACAAGAGAAAAAGCUUCUGCUACUAGAGUGUAUAUUGUUCUCGAUAAUUCUGGAUUUGAGCUUGUUACAGAUUUAAUAUUAGCCGACUUCUUGUUGUCCUCUGAACUGGCUACUGAGGUUCAUUUUUAUGGAAAAACAAUUCCAUGGUUUGUUUCUGAUACUACUAUACAUGAUUUUAAUUGGUUAAUUGAACAGGUAAAACACAGUAAUCAUAAGUGGAUGUCCAAGUGUGGGGCUGACUGGGAAGAGUAUAUUAAAAUGGGUAAAUGGGUUUACCACAAUCAUAUAUUUUGGACUCUGCCUCAUGAGUACUGUGCAAUGCCUCAGGUUGCACCUGACUUAUAUGCUGAACUACAGAAGGCACAUUUAAUUUUAUUCAAGGGUGAUUUGAAUUACAGGAAGUUGACAGGUGACAGAAAAUGGGAGUUUUCUGUUCCAUUUCAUCAGGCUCUGAAUGGCUUCCAUCCUGCACCACUCUGUACCAUAAGAACAUUAAAAGCUGAAAUUCAGGUUGGUCUGCAGCCUGGGCAAGGGGAACAGCUCCUGGCCUCUGAGCCCAGCUGGUGGACCACUGGAAAAUAUGGAAUAUUUCAGUACGAUGGUCCCCUUUGACUUGAUUUAGGAGCUCUCAGUUGCAUAGAAAGAUCUGGUGAGCACCUUUUCAUCCCCAGAAAAGGAGCACGUGAAUUGAGUCGCCUGGCGGCUCUGUACGCGCUCAGGGAAGCUUAGCUUCUUGGUGCCCAUCUACGUGCACUGGAUGAUUUUUCUUUUGAACAUUUUGCCCCACUACACUGUUUUGGGGAUAGCUGGGUUAAGCAAGUUAAAGAUAUUUACAUUUAUAUUGGAAUUUUAGCAACUUUUUUUCAGGUUAAAUAUAUAAUUUCAAGUGCUUUUAAUGAACUUAUUUUUAAUUGGCUAGGGAGCAAAAAAUAAGUGAGUUCUGCUUUUAGUUAGUUAACCUUGUUCUUUUCUUAAAUAGUACACUGCAUGGUAUUUAAUAUUCCAGGAAGCAUGGGAUUUUAUUUUGCUUGAUUUUGGGCACAUGAAAUAAUAGCUCUAGGAAAAUGCGCAUCUUAAUGACUCUUUGUAAAGAGAGGCAUUUCUUACAACUGUGAUGUUUGCUUACAUAAAAGUUACCUCAUAAGUUAAUUCUAACUUUUAUUCUUGAAUUUUAUUUCAUUUCAAUAGCUUGUUUCAUUUGCACGCCUUUGUAUUUUGAUUGACCUGUAGAAUGGAUGUUAGGAAACUCAAAAUUGAACACAGUGAAACAAAUGGUAUUUGAAGAAAUGUAAUAUCUUUUAUAUUCUAUUUAUGAUAUCCAUAAUCAAAUGAGAUUAUUUUACCACAUAAAUGUUUUAAAUAUCAGAUUUUUAGUUUGCAGUUUUAGGAAAAUGCUUUAGAUAGAAAAGGUUCUUAUGCAUUGAAUUUGGAGUACUACCAACAAUGAAUGAAUUUAUUUUUUAUAUUCUUACACAUUUUAUUGGUCAUUGUCACAGAUAGUAAAUACUAAAAAUUUCAGGUCAGUUUGUUUUGAAACUGAAAUUGGAAAUAAAUCUGGAAAUGUUUUGUUGCACUAAAAUAAUAAAAUGAAUUGUACUGAAAA